ACUUCAUGGCUUCUCACGCUUGUGCUGCAUAUCCCACACCAAUUAGACCCAAGGAUCAGUUGGAAGUUUCCAGGACAUCUUCAUUUUAUUUCCACCCUCAAUCCACAUUUCCAGAUGUCUCUGCAGCAAAGCGAAAUUCCAGGAGAAGAGGACAAAGAUACUCAGAGAGAAAAAGUAAAAGACCGAAGAAGGAGGCUGGAGAGACCAGGAUCCUUCCAGCUGAACAAAGUCAGCCACAAAGCAGACUAGCCAGCCGGCUACAAUUGGAGUCAGAGUCCCAAAGACAUGGGCUUGUUAGAGUGCUGUGCAAGAUGUCUGGUAGGGGCCCCCUUUGCUUCCCUGGUGGCCACUGGAUUGUGUUUCUUUGGGGUGGCACUGUUCUGUGGCUGUGGACAUGAAGCCCUCACUGGCACAGAAAAGCUAAUUGAGACCUAUUUCUCCAAAAACUACCAAGACUAUGAGUAUCUCAUCAAUGUGAUCCAUGCCUUCCAGUAUGUCAUCUAUGGAACUGCCUCUUUCUUCUUCCUUUAUGGGGCCCUCCUGCUGGCUGAGGGCUUCUACACCACCGGCGCAGUCAGGCAGAUCUUUGGCGACUACAAGACCACCAUCUGCGGCAAGGGCCUGAGCGCAACGGUAACAGGGGGCCAGAAGGGGAGGGGUUCCAGAGGCCAACAUCAAGCUCAUUCUUUGGAGCGGGUGUGUCAUUGUUUGGGAAAAUGGCUAGGACAUCCCGACAAGUUUGUGGGCAUCACCUAUGCCCUGACCGUUGUGUGGCUCCUGGUGUUUGCCUGCUCUGCUGUGCCUGUGUACAUUUACUUCAACACCUGGACCACCUGCCAGUCUAUUGCCUUCCCCAGCAAGACCUCUGCCAGUAUAGGCAGUCUCUGUGCUGAUGCCAGAAUGUAUGGUGUUCUCCCAUGGAAUGCUUUCCCUGGCAAGGUUUGUGGCUCCAACCUUCUGUCCAUCUGCAAAACAGCUGAGUUCCAAAUGACCUUCCACCUGUUUAUUGCUGCAUUUGUGGGGGCUGCAGCUACACUGGUUUCCCUGCUCACCUUCAUGAUUGCUGCCACUUACAACUUUGCCGUCCUUAAACUCAUGGGCCGAGGCACCAAGUUCUGAUCCCCCGUAGAAAUCCCCCUUUCUCUAAUAGCGAGGCUCUAACCACACAGCCUACAAUGCUGCGUCUCCCAUCUUAACUCUUUGCCUUUGCCACCAACUGGCCCUCUUCUUACUUGAUGAGUGUAACAAGAAAGGAGAGUCUUGCAGUGAUUAAGGUCUCUCUUUGGACUCUCCCCUCUUAUGUACCUCUUUUAGUCAUUUUGCUUCAUAGCUGGUUCCUGCUAGAAAUGGGAAAUGCCUAAGAAGAUGACUUCCCAACUGCAAGUCACAAAGGAAUGGAGGCUCUAAUUGAAUUUUCAAGCAUCUCCUGAGGAUCAGAAAGUAAUUUCUUCUCAAAGGGUACUUCCACUGAUGGAAACAAAGUGGAAGGAAAGAUGCUCAGGUACAGAGAAGGAAUGUCUUUGGUCCUCUUGCCAUCUAUAGGGGCCAAAUAUAUUCUCUUUGGUGUACAAAAUGGAAUUCAUUCUGGUCUCUCUAUUACCACUGAAGAUAGAAGAAAAAAGAAUGUCAGAAAAACAAUAAGAGCGUUUGCCCAAAUCUGCCUAUUGCAGCUGGGAGAAGGGGGUCAAAGCAAGGAUCUUUCACCCACAGAAAGAGAGCACUGACCCCGAUGGCGAUGGACUACUGAAGCCCUAACUCAGCCAACCUUACUUACAGCAUAAGGGAGCGUAGAAUCUGUGUAGACGAAGGGGGCAUCUGGCCUUACACCUCGUUAGGGAAGAGAAACAGGGUGUUGUCAGCAUCUUCUCACUCCCUUCUCCUUGAUAACAGCUACCAUGACAACCCUGUGGUUUCCAAGGAGCUGAGAAUAGAAGGAAACUAGCUUACAUGAGAACAGACUGGCCUGAGGAGCAGCAGUUGCUGGUGGCUAAUGGUGUAACCUGAGAUGGCCCUCUGGUAGACACAGGAUAGAUAACUCUUUGGAUAGCAUGUCUUUUUUUCUGUUAAUUAGUUGUGUACUCUGGCCUCUGUCAUAUCUUCACAAUGGUGCUCAUUUCAUGGGGUAUUAUCCAUUCAGUCAUCGUAGGUGAUUUGAAGGUCUUGAUUUGUUUUAGAAUGAUGCACAUUUCAUGUAUUCCAGUUUGUUUAUUACUUAUUUGGGGUUGCAUCAGAAAUGUCUGGAGAAUAAUUCUUUGAUUAUGACUGUUUUUUAAACUAGGAAAAUUGGACAUUAAGCAUCACAAAUGAUAUUAAAAAUUGGCUAGUUGAAUCUAUUGGGAUUUUCUACAAGUAUUCUGCCUUUGCAGAAACAGAUUUGGUGAAUUUGAAUCUCAAUUUGAGUAAUCUGAUCGUUCUUUCUAGCUAAUGGAAAAUGAUUUUACUUAGCAAUGUUAUCUUGGUGUGUUAAGAGUUAGGUUUAACAUAAAGGUUAUUUUCUCCUGAUAUAGAUCACAUAACAGAAUGCACCAGUCAUCAGCUAUUCAGUUGGUAAGCUUCCAGGAAAAAGGACAGGCAGAAAGAGUUUGAGACCUGAAUAGCUCCCAGAUUUCAGUCUUUUCCUGUUUUUGUUAACUUUGGGUUAAAAAAAAAAAAAGUCUGAUUGGUUUUAAUUGAAGGAAAGAUUUGUACUACAGUUCUUUUGUUGUAAAGAGUUGUGUUGUUCUUUUCCCCCAAAGUGGUUUCAGCAAUAUUUAAGGAGAUGUAAGAGCUUUACAAAAAGACACUUGAUACUUGUUUUCAAACCAGUAUACAAGAUAAGCUUCCAGGCUGCAUAGAAGGAGGAGAGGGAAAAUGUUUUGUAAGAAACCAAUCAAGAUAAAGGACAGUGAAGUAAUCCGUACCUUGUGUUUUGUUUUGAUUUAAUAACAUAACAAAUAACCAACCCUUCCCUGAAAACCUCACAUGCAUACAUACACAUAUAUACACACACAAAGAGAGUUAAUCAACUGAAAGUGUUUCCUUCAUUUCUGAUAUAGAAUUGCAAUUUUAACACACAUAAAGGAUAAACUUUUAGAAACUUAUCUUACAAAGUGUAUUUUAUAAAAUUAAAGAAAAUAAAAUUAAGAAUGUUCUCAAUCAAA